GGCGGCCGCUCCCAUGGGUGUCGCUGGGCCGCGCCAUGCCUAAGGGGGCGCCGCGAUGGGCCAAGGGGACGAGAGCGAGCGCAUCGUGAUCAACGUGGGCGGCACGCGCCACCAGACGUACCGCUCGACCCUGCGCACGCUGCCCGGCACGCGGCUCGCCUGGCUGGCGGAGCCCGACGCCCACAGCCACUUCGACUAUGACCCGCGUGCUGACGAGUUCUUCUUCGACCGCCACCCCGGCGUCUUCGCGCACAUCCUGAACUACUACCGCACGGGCAAGCUGCACUGCCCAGCCGACGUGUGCGGGCCGCUCUACGAGGAGGAGCUGGCCUUCUGGGGCAUCGACGAGACCGACGUGGAGCCCUGCUGCUGGAUGACGUACCGCCAGCACCGCGACGCCGAGGAGGCUCUGGACAGCUUCGGCGGCGCUCCUCUGGACAACAGCGCCGACGACGCGGACGCCGACGGCCCUGGCGACUCGGGCGACGGCGAGGACGAGCUGGAGAUGACCAAGCGCCUGGCGCUCAGUGACUCCCCGGAUGGCCGGCCUGGCGGCUUUUGGCGCCGCUGGCAGCCGCGCAUCUGGGCGCUCUUCGAGGACCCGUACUCGUCCCGCUACGCGCGGUAUGUGGCCUUCGCUUCCCUCUUCUUCAUCCUGGUCUCCAUCACCACCUUCUGCCUGGAGACCCACGAGCGCUUCAACCCCAUCGUGAACAAGACGGAGAUCGAGAACGUUCGCAAUGGCACGCAAGUGCGCUACUACCGGGAGGCCGAGACGGAGGCCUUCCUUACCUACAUCGAGGGCGUCUGUGUGGUCUGGUUCACCUUCGAGUUCCUCAUGCGUGUCAUCUUCUGCCCCAACAAGGUAGAGUUCAUCAAGAACUCGCUCAACAUCAUUGACUUUGUGGCCAUCCUGCCCUUCUACCUGGAGGUGGGGCUGAGCGGCCUGUCCUCCAAGGCAGCCAAGGACGUGCUGGGCUUCCUGCGCGUCGUCCGCUUCGUGCGCAUCUUGCGCAUCUUUAAGCUGACCCGCCACUUUGUGGGCCUGCGGGUCCUGGGCCACACGCUCCGAGCCAGCACCAACGAGUUCCUGCUGCUCAUCAUCUUCCUGGCCUUGGGCGUGCUGAUCUUCGCCACCAUGAUCUACUACGCCGAGAGGAUAGGGGCACAGCCCAAUGACCCCAGCGCCAGUGAGCACACGCACUUUAAGAACAUCCCCAUCGGCUUCUGGUGGGCCGUGGUCACCAUGACGACCCUGGGCUAUGGAGACAUGUACCCGCAGACGUGGUCCGGCAUGCUGGUGGGGGCUCUGUGUGCGCUGGCGGGCGUGCUCACCAUCGCCAUGCCCGUGCCCGUCAUCGUGAACAAUUUCGGGAUGUAUUACUCCUUAGCCAUGGCUAAGCAGAAACUACCAAAGAAAAAAAAGAAGCAUAUUCCGCGGCCACCGCAGCUGGGAUCUCCCAAUUAUUGUAAAUCUGUCGUAAACUCUCCACACCACAGUACUCAGAGUGACACAUGUCCGCUGGCCCAGGAAGAAAUUUUAGAAAUUAACAGAGCAGGUAGGAAACCUCUUAGAGGCAUGUCGAUCUGACCUUUCACCUCUGCCCCCUGUAGCGAUGAUUCCAGAUCCAGUCAGACUGCUUCCUUAGUUCCGUGGGUGACCCCGGACCCCGCACUCAGUCUGGAGGUGUGGAGCCUGGGGGCCCAGGGAGAUGCUGGGCGGCCAAAUUCAGCAGGCAAGAGCCUGCUAGAGGAACCUCACUGGUGCCCCUGGGUAAGGAGGUUGACGCGGUUGGUCUCGUGAUGUUCUGAAGAGACAACGCGGCCCGCCAGGUUGCUGAGGACUAACUUAGCAGGAGCCAGGGGGGCUCUGCUUGGUGGGGCAGGAGUCCGGUGUGAGUCUCUGACUCAGGCUACUGACCCGGUGUUGGGACAGAGUGGGGGCGGGUGUGAUUUGGAAACGCUAGACAGCCUUUGAUCUGGUCCUUACCAUGGCUCCCUUCAGGCUGUGUAGAUGGCAGAGAUGGUGCAUGGGAUCUGGGCAGGAGGGUCCCUUGCAAAGGCAGGUGCAAGGGUUCUCACCCCCGGCAGAGCCUGUCUCCAUAGCUGAGUAGAAUUCCUGCCCUGAUUUCGGGCUGCCCAGCUCGAGGUCCUUCCCAGGAGACGCCUGUAGCCCUCCGUGACAAGCUUACUUACCCCAUAGCAUGCUGAACCAACUCAUCUUCUACCACCACUCUAGAGUUUAGCCUUUAUCUUUAGGAACCUGUUGAAGUGACUCUAGCUUUCACGUUGUCUGUUUGGGUUGAUGGUCGAGUGGGAGUUUCCGGUGACCCGAUGGAAGCGGCUGCCGAGCAAAAGACUAGAGGGGGCCACCACCCUGGGCAGCUUAGAUGAAAGCGCUACAGACCAGCAACAGCCUCCCACCGAGGGUUCUCCCCGUUUCCAGCGGUAGGGACUGCAGCAGCAAUAUAGACAUCCCAACCAGUGUACAACCACUUUCCCGUGAAUUCACUGGGGGCCGGGAGGGGGGAGGGGGGCAUGAAACAAUACUAGUCACCGUGGGAUAUAUUCUAAUAUUCCAUGGCUAGUGGUUUGUUAUGGGACUAUCUCAGUUUUAUGAGAACCUGCACAUAGCACAUAAAGUUGAUCAUGGGGCUCUGGUCCGAAGAUAUAAAGCCCAUAGUCUACCUCUACCCAUGGAAUACCAUCGACUUAUUCUGUGGACACAGGGAUUUCAAAGGAACAGAUGACCCAGAGAAGAAUGACAGCACUGAGUAAGAAGGAGUGCCAGGUGAGCAGGAGGUUGACGUGACAGGUGGCAUUUAGUCUAUGAAGGACCUCCCCAUGCCCAGGUCUGGCAGGAGGCUGCUGGCUAGCUCAGCCCCAGGUGGGGAAGUUUCCCCCUGGUUUGGGUGGCCUCCCCCAGUGGAUGAUUGAUUUUCUUCCCUGCUAUCGCGCUCUCUGACCCACCACCCCAUCCCAAUCCUCUUCUGGCUUUACCCCACAGCUAUGCUGGCCCGAGCACUACCCUCAAGGCCCAUUUCUUUGCCCAUGGGGGUUUCCCGGUCCUUUCACCCUGCCGCAUACCCUUCCCUUCCUGGGAUUUCUGUAGGUGCCUGAGAGGAACAUGGCCAGGGGUCUCCGAGGCUGAAACAGCUCCGAGCUCUCUGCUUUGGAUUAGCUAGUUACUUGAUUUCAGGAGCUACCAACAGGGCUCUGGGCCUCUAGGAGGAACGCGUGGGCUGGCCCAGGCCCCAGCUUCCAUGUGGGCCUGGCAAGAAGAGCUCAGCCUGAGUGGCAUCACUGUGGCACUACCUGGCCCUUCCCCUGCAUCCUCCCCGACACUGGAUCUUUCAGGAGUGUUGCCCCAAGCACAGGUGCCCUGGGCCAGCCAGUCAAGAAUCCCCAGUGCUCUCCAGGCAGGCCCAGAUUCCUCUGUACUCUUGGACAAUGACAGUAUUAUCCUGUGCGGAGUCCCCCUGCCCCCCAGGGAGUGCAGAUGUGUUUGUUCAGACAUGCACACCAGCUAAUCCCAGGACACAAAACCUGUAAAACCCAUGCACUCCUGUGGGAUUGCCCCUGAGCUCCACAGUCUCUCCCCAGCCCUGCUUUUGAGAGCCACUUUGCCCUGGUCCCAGGUUUCAGGGGCCCAGACAGUUCUGGCUUGGACAGUCUCUGUGGCUGAGGAAGUAUUUGGGGCCCUCACAAGCUUGCCCUCUGGAGCUUGGAUGCCUGGAUCCCUCCUGCCUCCCCCGUCACCAACUGUGCUCCCAAGCCCUUCCCAAGCACUCACUUCCCGGUGGUGUUGGUGCUGUCCUGAUAUCCUGACCCCCGAGGCUCCAGCCUCAUCCCUCACCAGAACACUUCUCCCUCCAAAAGCUGGCGUGUGAGACCCCGGCUAUCCGCCACCAAGAGGAGUUGCGGUCUUUAGGGGCGUUGUCCCCACCUCUGCACCCCAGAGUUCUUCCCAUUCACCUUUUUUCCUGCUUGCAGCCAUGCACCUAGAUGGGCAUAGGGUUGGGGUGAGUUUGUGGGAGAGUGAGGGGGAGGCCAGGGGCAAGGAAGGUAAAUGUGGUGGCCCCACAGGAAUUGUGAGAGAUGAGAUGCAGCCCCCCAAGGCCUUUCCAGUCUCACUGUACCCCCAAGGCAGUCUAGUGGCCUCGCCAAAACCUGAGCUUCUCCAAUUCCACUUUUAAAACCAGAGUUAGGGGCUGUGUGUGGCACGCUGGGUUCUGAGGGCAUCCCUCCCGCCCCCCCAGGCCAGCCCCCAGUGGUGCCAGCAGCACCUGCCCCUCACCUCCACCUCUUGGUCUCGUCUGAAGCCUCAGUCUGUGUGUCUGUCCCAGGGACAAUCUGGUCUCCUCCUGUGUGCUGUGGCUGGCAUGGCCUCAGUGUCUGAGGGCUUGUCCUGGGAGGGGUAUCAAGAAUCCAAUUCUCACCUGGUUGUAGGACCUCUUGGGGGAUGCUAGGAGGGCGCCCUGGCACAGCCAGGGAUUGCCUAGGGCUGAGGGGCCCAGGAGAAGCUACUUCUCUCCCAGAAAGGGGCUCCCUCCUGCAUCUGCAGUCGGAUGCCCAGACCGCCCACUCUGGACAGCCCACAAUGCCUCCUCCGUCCUGCCAUGCCCAUUCGCAUGUGUCUUGUCCAUCUCCGCUCCUGUGAUGUGGGUCAGUCCUUUGUGGUGCCGCGUCCAGGGCUGCAGGGUCCCACGUCAGUGAGCAGUGGGUGGCCGGUGGAGGGGGUGGUGGUGGCCGGGCUCCCUUCCUGCCCAUGGCACCUAGAACAGCAGUGAGGUCUCAGAGAAGCCCCCGCCUGGGCUCCCUGGGAGCUAACCUUGCAGCCUCUGGGUUAUCUUUGGCAAAGGGGUCUAAAGUCCCCUAUCCCCAGCCCCUCUACUUCCCCUGCUGGGCAGCAGUGGCUGCCCAGUGAGUGGUGCUAUCCAUGGAGGGGGGAGGGAGCUGGGCAGCGCUGACUAGGCGGCGGGUGGGGCUAAGAGAGUUUCUGCAGGGACCCAGCUGCAGGGUCAGCAGCCUGUGGGCCCUGAGUGGGGUCUUUGUUGUCCUCAGGUGGGCUGUGGGGGAAGUAGCGGAGAAAUGAAGUGACGCCAGGGGCCAGGCAUGGGUGUUCUUUUCCGUGUUGUUCACAUUUUCUCUCUUUCUCUCUCUCUCCACUAAUCAUGUUUCUCUCUCUCUCCUCGUUUUGUUGCAUGACUUGUGCCGGUUCUCGUGAUUGUUCCCUGCUCGUGUCUCACAGACUGUCCCCAUUUAGCCUGAGACUUUUUUCCUGAGUCCCCAGCUGGGCAGAUCCCUCAGGGCUAAACCCAAGGAAAUGCCCAGCAACCCCCAACCCACCCCAGCCCCGCGUGCGCCCCUCCGGUGCCCGCAGCUGGUGUGAACAGUAAGUACUUUGGCGGUGCCUGGAGACCAGGGCAGAAAAGCCAGCUGUGCUGACUGAGGGCCCAGCCUCGGGUUCUCCUUGCUCCAAAGUUUAAAAAAAAAUGACCCUCUCGCAGAUGCUCAUCUCAGCCCAUUUCAAGCCUGGAAACCAUCUCUGAGACGCUGCCCAUGCUGCCAUUUCAUCACUGCAGGCCUGUGGGUCUAGUGGGGGCCUGGGGGCCCUGGGCUGGGGGAGGCAGGGCCCCCAGCCUCUGGAAAGCAGGUGGGAAUGGAGGCUCCUAGCCACUAUCUCAUCCAAAGGAUGGGGCAGGGGCGGGGGCUCACACCUUUGACCCUAUUCAUGGGUUCCCCAGAUUUAUACAGUUGGCCCCUCGUUGGUUUCUCUUUCUUCAAGCCACCCCUCUGGAGUUGGGGAGGGAGAAUGCCCCAGUUUCUGAAAGCAUCUUAAACCAUAGAUAGACGAACAGCCCAGGGGCCUGGGCCCCUUCACAGAGCAAGACUUAAGCUUCCCCACCCAAUCAUUAGUCCCUCCUCAAAGGUUAGGGUUGAGAGAAGCAGUAGGCCCUAGGGGUGUCCCGGGAAUCCCCCAGGAGGGAAAGGUGCCAGGCUAUCAUCCCUCCAGGGAUCCCUGAUGGAUGUUCCUUGUCCCCUGCCCAAAACCAUCCCGAACUUUGGGCCCUUUAGUGAUUGUGAGAGCUGGGAGCCCCCAGGGCCUGGGGGCUUGUGGACAGAACCAGUGGGCGGGGGCCCAGCAUUCAGAGCCAGAGAAGGGUCUCAGGCGGCACCAUCUCCACAGAGGCAGAGGCAGAGAGAAGGCACCCCCCUCUGACCCACCCCUCCCCAGGCAAGAACUGCAGGCUGUGGACACCUCCCCUGGCAGAGGAUGGCCAACAGAGACUCAGCAAGUCCUCACUCCCCUCCCAGAAGGAGACGCUGCCUGGGAGGACCCACUGUUCUCCCCUUGAGGAAAAUCCAUGCAGGGUGCUAUGGGCCUCAACCCCCACAUCGUCAUCCGCGUCCUCUCCAUACUGUUUCCCUCCCCUCUCCCAACACCCUCCUCCCUCAGCCCGGAGACCCUUGGAUGGAAGACUGGGCCAGCCAGAGUGGGAGGCAGGACCAGCGUGUCUGCGAGCACACGUGUGUGCCUGCAGACAUGCCCCAAGACCCCAGAGACGCCCCGGCCCCAGUCACAUGGUGUCAGAGUUACCUUGGCAACUGGCCUUUUUGGUUCAGAGUAAAUUGGGAAGUGAAGCCCCUGGGAUUUGUCGAGAAACGCACUGUACGUGAAAUGCUUUGCCAUCUUGUACGAAAGACUUUUUUUUUAAGUUCCAAAAUUAUGAUGGGAUUUUUUUGGAUUUGCUUUACGAAUAAAUCUGAUUGGUCCAUUUCUCUUUUGA